UGUGGGCUCAAGUGAUCCUCCCGCUUCGGCUGGGAUUACAGCCCACGAAGUGCUGGGAUUACAGGCAUGAGCCGUCACUCCGGACCCUAUAGACCUUAGUAUCCCCUCAUGGCUCUUUCAUUCCCAAGUAAAUUCAGAGGUGUCCAUGAGAGGUCAGGGGUCACUUCCCAUUGAACCACACAGACAGGUCCUGCUUGCAGUAUUUCUGCCUUCAGCCCAUGUAGAGAGCUUUCAUGCCAUUUCCUGCUUAAAACCCUUUACUCACUUCCCACCCUGUGCCUUGUAAGGUCCUCACCCGCGAGGUGCAUUCACCCUUUGGGUCCCCUAAGCCUCGCCCUUCAUUGCGUCUGCACAGCAGCACCGCAGCUCCGGUGCAAGAGAGUCCUCGCCCUGGUCCUGGGAUUCCACAGAUCCCACCCCUCCCCUGAGACACCCUCCCAUCUUGCUCUCAUUGAGCCUUGCCCUCUAUCCUGCAGGCCUCCCCCUCAUAAGCAUGGCUUCCUCUGACCCAGCGUUGAAGGAGGUGACUUGGGCCUGUCUGUUCACCUCCAAUGUUCUUUUGUCCCAGAUUCCACUCCACUAGGAAAAGUGCUUUCAGUAGGUGGGCAUCUUAUUCCAUCCCCUUCCCUGUAAAUAUGUGGCCACAGGGGAUCAGGAGAAAGAGAGACAGGAGAAAGAGGAAAUAGAAAAACUGAGAAGGAGUGAGAAGGACGGGUGAGAACCAUGAACAGAUGGCAACGCAGAGGAUGGGUGGGGAAUUUGCAGACAGACACUGAGAGUGAAAGACAAAGCUGAGAAAGUGUGGGGCAGGGAGCAACUGGAGAAAUAUAGAGAAAAGCUGGGUCUCCAGAGAGAUGAAGGACAGCAAGAUAGGGAGAGGGGCAGAAAGGGGGAGGCUCCUCAGACAGAGAGUGGGGGAGAGGAGGAGGAAUUUGGAGUCAGGGCAGACAGCAAUGUGGUGCUGGGACAGCAAGACGGGACAGCUGGUGACAAGGAGAGCAGAGGGAGAACCACAGUAUGGGAAGGCUUUGGAUCUGGGGGUGCCAGAGAGUGGGGACAAGGGGUGUAACAGGGAAGAGGGGAUUUAAUAGGGGGAGCAGAGGGGGAGCAAAGAUGAGGGAAGAAAGAGGCAGAAAUAUGUGGAGAUUGGGAUUGGGACAAUGAAAAGUUUGGGCAGAAAGGAAUAAGAGGUGGAAGAAGUUGUAGGAAUGGAGCAGAACAGGGGGAAGAGAAGGAAUGGAGGGAAGAAGGGGAGAAAGAGCAGGAGAGGAGAGGGGCUCAAAAUGAGGAGCAGAAACCUGGGGGGAAACAUCGGAAAAAAAGAGCCAGGGAGGGAAGGUGAGGAUGAGAUAUGUACAGAAUGAGAGAGGGAAACACACAGGAAGGAAGAAGGAGGGGACCUUGGUUCAGGUGAGUGGUGAGUUGAUUGAAUAUGGGUAAUUUAGUUGUGACAUGUUGAUUUCUGUCUUUAUAAUCUAACAGAUUUUAAAUAUGCUUAAAAUACACAGAUAAAGAUGAGAAUUGCAAAACUUGUCUAUAAGGCUAUGCAUUUUAUAAUUAUGGCAUCAGAGGUUAGCUUCCACUUGUAACCUUUUCAGCCAGAGGGCAGUGACUUGACUCAUUCAUUUGUGGGCCACGCUCUUCCUCCAUUUCCCUGGGAUGGGGUUGGGUAGGGGCGAGAACAUGAGUUAAUGUAAUACUGAUUACAUAAUAUUUAGUAUUAUAUGAUGCUGAUUAUAGUCAAUAUAAUAGUGUACAGUCAAUGUAAUAGUGAACACUCCACACAGAAAACUCAUCACCAAAAUGUGGAGGAACUUCUUCCCACCAGCAAUGCAUUUUCCAUCCGACACUAACUGGGUGAACUUAUACUUCAACUCAAUUCUGACACUGUCCAGCUAGAAUUAGGAUCAGAUGCUGUUUACUGGUUGGUCAGUUCCACAGGGCUACCCCCACUUCAAAUGCCGGUCACAAGUUGCAGGUUGGGACCUGAACUUCUGGGCGACCAACUGUAAAUUGGGGAUUCACUUGACCCCCCUCCUCAGGUUGUAGUAAUUUGCCACGGUCAUUCACCGAACUCAGGACAACACUUAGUUUACUCAUUUAUUAUAAAGUAUGUUGCAAAGGACACAGAUGAACAGCCAGAUGGAAAAGCUGUGCUAGCUAGUUAUUCAAACCCAAGGAAAGUGUUAGGGAAGCACAUUGACCAGGUCAGUCAGAGCGUACAGCAUAUGAAGUGAGGGCAGUCCUGUGCGACUGAACCCUCAAGCUGUGGUGUCUGAUUCUGUUUUGUAGACGGUGUCAGAAUUGAGUAAAACAGCAGGACUCCCUACCUGGGAGUCUGCUGGAGAAGCUGUCAUUGUGGGGACAAUGACACACAUUUUGGUGACUAGAGGUGAAAUAUUCUGUGUUAGAGUGUCAGAGUAGUAUGAACAAUUUUUUUCCUCUCUGAACAGAUCUCCAAUGCAUGAUAAAGCCUUUUUUUCUUCUACUCUUCCAUCUUUAAGACAAAAAAAUACUUUCAACUACAUUUCCCUCUGUAAUAAGUACCUAUUUGUGCUCUAUUUAAGAGCAUAAUAUUCUAAAAACUAGUUUUACUUUGUCUUCAAUUCUUUUUUUUUUUUUAAAUAAAAAUAUAGAGACAGGAUCUUGCUGUGUUGGCCAGGCUGGUCUCAAACUCCUGGGCUCAAGUAGUCUUUCCACCUCAACCUCCCAAAGUACUGGGAUUACAAGCGUGAGCCGUGUGCGGCCACUUUGUCUUCAAUUAUUGCUUAAACCUUUGAAUUGUUGCUUGAAUCUAGCUUUCACAUCCAGCAUUCCACUGAUUCUUCCUUUUUCAGUCAUCAGUGACCUCCCAAUUCCUAAAUGCCGUAAUUCAUGUCCUGUCCUCAUCUUUUUCUUCCUGUCGGUAGCAUGUAGCACAGCUGAUCACUUCCUCUUCUGUUAUCUUGGCUUUUAUGACACCCCGUUAACCUUUACAAAUCUAUUCAAUCUUCUUGCCACUCUGAUCACUUUCUGCUUUCCUCUUCUGGUGUCUCCAGAACUUUCUUGUUCUCUGAAUGUGCAAGUGCUCAUGGCUCAGUCCUUACACCUCUUCUUGUCUCCGUCCACACCCACUGCCUUUCCGUACUUCUCAUCUCAUGGCUUUAUGCCCCACCUGUUAAUACUCAGCCCCAUGUACCCUGCAGACCCUCCUCUGAGGUCUAGAAUCCUGUGUCUAGUUGUCUCCAAAACUCUCUACAGGGAUGUCCCAACAGGCAUCUCCAUUUUCAUAUGCCUAAAAGUGACUUCUUGGCUGGGCACAGUGGCUCAUGCCUAUAAUCCCAGCACUUUGGGAGGCCGAGGCAGGCGGAUCACCUGAGGCCAGGAGUUUGAGACCAGCCUGGCCAACAUGGCGAAACCCUAUCUCUACUAAAAAUACAAAAAAUUAGCCGGGCGUGGUGGCGGGCGCCUGUAAUCCCAGCUACUCAGGAGGCUGAGGCAGGAGAAUCGCUUGAACCCAGGAGGCGGAGGCUGCAGUGAGCCGAGAUCACGCUACUGCACUCCAGCCUGGGCAACAAGAGUGAAACUCUCUCAAAAAUUAAUUAAUUAAUUAUUUAAAUAAAAGUGACUUCCCAAACUCCUCCAAACAUAUUCACCCCUGCAGUCUUGCACAUCUCAGCUAAGGGCAACCCUGUACUUCCUGGGGCUCAGCUGAACUUCUUGUCAUGUUUAAAAUAUGCAAGAUACUAUGUUGUAAGUGUGUUACUUUGUAAAAUGAAGAAAAAAUUAAGCAUUUACUUAAAACAGGUGAGGAAAUACAUGGUUUCAUAAAUUUUUUUGACGUAUGGGAGAAAGAAUGUUUGAAGACCUCUCCCUGCGUGAUCUGCACCCUCAGGACCUCUCAGACGCCAUCUCCUUCCUGUGUCCUCCCAGCCCCCUCUGCUCCAGUCACACAGGCCCCUUUCCUUUUCCUGGAGCCAAGGUUGCUCCUGCCUCAAGGCUUCCAUGUGGGCUGGCCCUCUGCCUAGAACUCCCUGGCCUCUCAGCUGCAAGUGACAAGCAGCCUUUCUUCCUGAGGUCUUUGUUCUGACAUCACUUCCUCCGUGGAAACGUUUGUGAUCUCCCACAGCCUCCUAUUUGACAUUGCAGGCCCACCUUCACCCCCACCUCUGGUCCAUGUUGCCUGUUCUGUGUGAUUCUUUUUGCUCCUUCAAUAUCCAGUCUGGAUCCUGGUGAGAACAAGUCCCCAACAGGAGAGCAGAGCCAGAAGGUGGGGCUGUGCUGGGCUCACCCCCUCAGUGGAGCUCAACCCUGGCUUCAUAUUAGAGUGCCUAGGCGUUUUGCAGAAACAUCUCUUGUGCCCCCUUGACGUAUUUUCAUUUCAGUGUUUUAGAGCCCAGCUGAGUAAUAUUUAAAGUUGACUCUAUUCUGUAGCCAGCAUAGUACCAAUCACUGUCUUUUGUUUCUGAAGGCUGAGCUCAGCCUGGGAUCCACAGAGAGGUGAGGGGGGCUGUGUUCUGCAUGGGGUUUGGUCAGGGCUGGGUCUGUGUCCUAAAGGGGAGCUCAGUCCAGCCCAGCUCCCCACUGCUGCAGUGUGUGUGGGCUUCUCCAGGAGGAAGGUGGGUUCUGAAGAAAGGGGUCAGAAACUCACUUCUUCCUGUAGGAGUUUCUCGUCCCCGUAUUCCCCCUGGUGCAGUGGGGCGCAGAGGACCAUCUUUCCACAGGGUGAGAUCUGUGCGUGUGACUGUGGCACAUGAAGGGGAUGUAUAGAUUCUCAGCCCUAAGCAGCAUAUUUUGGAUAUUCAGUAUUGACUUCUAAAGACUCUUUUAUGUUACCCAAGGAAGAAGUCUGGAAGAAGAGGAAGAGGAAAGAAAAGGAGUCAGGGAUGGCCCUUACUCAGGUACGGUUGACAUUUAGGGAUGUGGCCAUAGAAUUCUCUCAGGAGGAGUGGAAAUGCCUGGACCCUGCUCAGAGGAUCUUAUACAGGGACGUGAUGUUGGAGAACUACUGGAACCUUGUUUCUCUGGGACUGUGUCAUUUUGAUAUGAAUAUUAUCUCCAUGUUGGAGGAAGGGAAAGAGCCCUGGACUGUGAAGAGCUGUGUGAAAAUAGCAAGAAAACCAAGAACGCCGGAAUGUGUCAAAGGCGUGGUCACAGAUAUCCCUCCUAAAUGUACAAUCAAGGAUUUGCUACCAAAAGAGAAGAGCAGUACAGAAGCAGUAUUCCACACAGUGGUGUUGGAAAGACACGAAAGCCCUGACAUUGAAGACUUUUCCUUCAAGGAACCCCAGAAAAAUGUGCAUGAUUUUGAGUGUCAAUGGAGAGAUGACACAGGAAAUUACAAGGGAGUGCUUAUGGCCCAGAAAGAAGGUAAAAGAGAUCAACGCGACAGAAGAGACAUAGAAAACAAGCUUAUGAACAAUCAGCUUGGAGUAAGCUUUCAUUCUCAUCUGCCUGAACUGCAGCUAUUUCAAGGUGAGGGGAAAAUGUAUGAAUGUAAUCAAGUUGAGAAGUCUACCAACAAUGGUUCCUCAGUGUCACCACUUCAACAAAUUCCUUCUAGUGUCCAAACCCACAGGUCUAAAAAAUAUCAUGAACUUAACCAUUUUUCAUUACUCACACAAAGACGAAAAGCAAACAGUUGUGGAAAACCUUAUAAAUGUAAUGAAUGUGGCAAGGCGUUCACUCAGAAUUCGAACCUUACAAGUCAUAGGAGAAUUCAUAGUGGAGAGAAGCCUUACAAAUGCAGUGAGUGCGGCAAAACCUUUACUGUUCGUUCAAAUCUAACUAUUCAUCAGGUCAUCCAUACUGGAGAAAAACCUUACAAAUGUCAUGAGUGUGGCAAGGUCUUCAGGCACAAUUCAUACCUUGCAACUCAUCGGCGAAUUCAUACUGGAGAGAAACCUUACAAGUGUAAUGAGUGUGGAAAAGCCUUUAGAGGACAUUCAAACCUAACUACCCAUCAGUUAAUUCAUACUGGAGAAAAACCGUUCAAAUGUAAUGAAUGUGGCAAGCUCUUCACUCAAAAUUCACACCUUAUAAGUCAUUGGAGAAUUCACACUGGAGAGAAACCUUACAAGUGCAAUGAGUGCGGCAAAGCCUUUAGUGUUCGUUCAAGCCUAGCAAUCCAUCAGACAAUCCACACUGGAGAAAAACCUUACAAAUGUAAUGAAUGUGGCAAAGUCUUUAGGUACAAUUCAUACCUCGGAAGGCAUCGGAGAGUUCAUACUGGUGAGAAACCUUACAAGUGUAAUGAAUGUGGCAAAGCCUUCAGUAUGCAUUCAAACCUAGCUACCCAUCAGGUCAUCCAUACUGGAACAAAACCUUUCAAAUGCAAUGAAUGCAGCAAGGUUUUCACUCAAAAUUCACAACUUGCAAAUCAUCGAAGAAUUCAUACUGGAGAGAAACCUUACAAGUGUAAUGAGUGUGGGAAAGCCUUCAGUGUUCGUUCAAGUCUGACUACCCAUCAGGCAAUCCAUUCUGGAGAGAAACCUUACAAAUGUAUUGAAUGUGGCAAGAGCUUCACUCAAAAAUCACACCUUAGAAGUCAUCGGGGAAUUCAUUCUGGAGAGAAACCUUACAAGUGUAAUGAAUGUGGUAAAGUCUUCGCUCAAACAUCACAACUUGCAAGGCAUUGGAGAGUUCAUACUGGAGAAAAACCUUACAAGUGUAAUGACUGUGGCAGAGCCUUUAGUGAUCGUUCAAGCCUAACUUUUCAUCAGGCAAUACAUACUGGAGAGAAACCUUACAAAUGUCAUGAAUGCGGCAAGGUUUUUAGGCACAAUUCAUACCUUGCAACUCAUCGGCGAAUUCAUACUGGAGAGAAACCUUACAAGUGUAAUGAGUGUGGGAAAGCCUUUAGUAUGCAUUCAAACCUAACUACCCAUAAGGUCAUCCAUACUGGAGAGAAGCCUUACAAAUGUAAUCAAUGUGGCAAGGUCUUCACUCAGAACUCACACCUUGCAAAUCAUCAAAGGACUCACACCGGAGAGAAACCUUACCGAUGCAAUGAGUGUGGGAAAGCCUUCAGUGUUCGUUCAAGCCUAACCACCCAUCAGGCAAUCCAUACUGGGAAAAAACCUUACAAAUGUAAUGAAUGUGGCAAGGUCUUUACUCAAAAUGCUCACCUGGCAAAUCACCGAAGAAUUCAUACUGGGGAGAAACCUUACAGGUGUACAGAGUGUGGGAAAGCCUUUAGGGUAAGAUCAAGUCUAACUACCCAUAUGGCAAUCCACACUGGAGAAAAGCGUUACAAAUGUAAUGAGUGUGGCAAGGUCUUCAGGCAGAGUUCAAAUCUUGCAAGUCAUCACAGAAUGCAUACCGGAGAGAAACCUUACAAAUGAGUGUGGUGAGGUCAUUAGGUACAAUUCACUCCUUUCACAUCAGUUAAUUUCAUUCUUGACAGAAUCCUUACAAAUGUAGUGACAGUGGCCAAUCCCUCAUGAGUUGAAGCAUUAAUAGAUAUGAGAGGCCAUAAGCAAGAGACAUCAUGUAAACAUAUGUGGCAGAGGGUCUAUCCAGGCCUCGCAGGUUACUAGGCAUCAAGAUUUAUAUCUUUGAUGAAACGAAACAAAUGUAAUAUGCAUCCUGAGGCCAUUACCCAGUGACCGAUGGUAAGUGAGGAUUCCUAGGAGGAAUAACAGUCUCUGGUUUCCCUGUUUGCCUUUGAUAUUAUACACUGUAGAAUACUCACAAGUCCAAAUAUGCUAAAAAUUAUAUAUUUUUAACUCACAUACGAAAAGGUUGCAGGAUAUUUGUAGGCAGUCAGUUACCUUCACCUUAUGAAAUGUUUCACUGAGUUAUUUGAGGUUUUUUGGAAAGCCUACUAUUGCGUUUCAAUGUGAACUUUGAAAUCUUAUUGUGCAUCCUUACACACCUUCCAUGGUGCUUUCUUGGAAAGAUCAUUGGGAUGGAAGGAUCAUUGAUUGGGUGAAGAUCAUUGAUUAGGUGAAGGAUUAUUUCUAUCCAAUUUGUGAAGAAGGAGGACUUUGCUUUUAAAAUUAAGUAUCAUCUGAAUUAGCAUUUGGGAGUGGCGAAAAACAAUGUAAAACUAUGAUGUCACUCACCAUUCUGAUAAUGUUCAGGGUGCCUUUCUCCUACCAGGAGAGUACUGUGGCUUAGAGGAAAGAAAUGGUCUAUCAACUGAACAUGAAAUGGAGCAGGCCAAGACCUUAGGACAUUGGGAUUUUUGUGGGAGGAGAGUAAUAGGUAAUUAGACACUGAUUGUGUGGUAGAAAUACUGCAGGGGAAAAGGUCGCCCUCUUAUGCAUCAAAGAGCAAUACCUGUUGUUUAGCAAAGAGUGAUGAAAAAUUGAUCUUGUUUUGAAAUUGAAGAGAGAGGCCAGGCGCGGUGGCUCACACCUGUAAUCCCAGCACUUUGGGAGGCUGAGGCAGGUGGAUCACCUGAGGUCGGGAGUUCGAGACCAGCCUGACCAACAUGGAGAAACCCCAAUUGUACUAAAAAUACAAAAUUAGCCGGGCGUGGUGGCAGGUGCCUGUAAUCCCAGCUACUUGGGAGGCUGAGGCAGGAGAGUGCUUGAACCCAGGAGGCGGAGGUUGUGGUGAGCCAAGAUCAUGCCACUGCACUCCAGCCUGGGCAACAAGAACAAAACUCCAUCUAAAGAAGAAAAAGAAAAACUGAAGAGAGAGUAGUUGUCAGAGUGAAGAGUUUAAUCAACAGAAGUAGAGUAACAUAUUCUUUAGUAGAACUCACAUUAUCUGCUUGAAGCACAUUUUGCUAAUGUUUUAUUCAGAAUGUAUCAUAGAUAUAAUGUUUUAACUAAUAAAAUAGAAUGGUUUUUCUCUA